ACCCUUCCUGCCUAUGCUAUGGCUGGAUGAACACAGAUGUGAGGGGAUUUGAACCAUCUACAAUCAAUCCAUAUGUGACCAAUGGAGGAGAAGCAGCCCCAAAAGACGAAGGAACCCUCAAAAGAAGAUGAGCCUCAGCAGAAGGAGAUGCCAACCCAUUUGUCCUUAGGAGCAGAGUCAAAGGCAGAGGCUAAAACUCCAGUUCUGGUUGAGACACAGACAGUGGACAAUGCCAAUGAGAAAUCAGAAAAACCCCCAGAAAACCAAAAGAAGCUCUCUGACAAAGAUACGGUAGCCACCAAGAUCCAGGCCUGGUGGCGGGGCACCCUGGUGCGUCGGGCACUGUUGCACGCAGCCCUCAGUGCCUGCAUCAUUCAGUGCUGGUGGCGGCUGAUACUGUCCAAGAUUCUGAAGAAGAGGCGGCAGGCAGCGCUAGAGGCCUUCUCCCGGAAGGAGUGGGCAGCAGUCACACUGCAGUCCCAGGCCCGCAUGUGGCGCAUCCGCAGACGCUAUUGCCAGGUGCUCAAUGCUGUUCGCAUCAUCCAGGCUUACUGGAGGUGCCGCUCCUGUGCUUCCCGGGGGUUCAUCAAGGGCCAGUACAGAGUCACAGCCAACCAGCUGCAUCUCCAGCUGGAGAUCUUGCUGGACUCAGGGCCUUGCAUUGUGACAGAGUGUAUUCCCUUCUCAAUAAAGGAAUGAAGUGGUCUUUUCCA